AGACGUGUGGCCAUGGUUUUAAUCAGGACAAUUUUUUGCUUGCUCUAACUUAUGAGGGUGGCCAGAUCUAGACAGACAGCAGAAGUAACCCGAAGUCCUGGCCUGCCCUGUGCCAUCCUCUGACAUGUUAUCAUCGGCGUUCACUCUGUGGGCUCCUCUCGGGGUGAUGCCUGCCGGUCUCAGCUUUGGGGUGAAGUGACAUUUGGCCUUGACUAGAAGAGGCAGGUUGUGGGGGGCAGGCAGGGUGCAGGCGAGGGAACUGAGGCAGAGCGGGCUGGGAGCAGGGGGGAUGUAGGGUCCUCCCAGGCUGACCCCCAGAACCUGGGCGUGCAGGCCUGCUCUGGGGUCCAGGCUCCGAUGCAGUCUCAGCGCAGGCCCUGGUGGCCGGAGACAGGGCAGGGCAGGAGCUUCAGGCCACCCGCACCGGCAGCCCUCAAGGCUGCCUUGAUGGAAUCGGACCCAGAUGGACUCUAAGCGGCCUCCUGCUUGGAAACCCUGUCAGACCCUGCGUUUUCUACAGAGCGGCUGUCACACGGCUUUUCCGGACGGUGAUUAUGGACUGCGUGUGGGAUUGGCGGGCCAGGUGAAUGAGAAGAUGUAGUGUGACAGCAGCCCGGGUGACACCUGCUGGGAGCUUGGCGUGGACACCCCAGCCACCCCCAGCCCAGCCCAGCCGGAGCACCCUACCCCUGGGCAUCCCCCUGGCCAUCCAGCCUCACCAUGUCCAAGAGGGGCAUGAGCAGCCGGGCCAAGGGGGACAAGGCAGAGGCCCUCGCGGCGCUGCAGGCGGCCAACGAGGAUCUUCGAGCCAAGCUCACAGACAUCCAGAUCGAGCUGCAGCAGGAGAAGAGCAAGGUCAGCAAAGUGGAACGCGAGAAGAACCAGGAGCUGCGGCAGGUGCGCGAGCAUGAGCAGCAUAAGACCGCGGUCUUGCUCACGGAGCUCAAGACAAAGCUGCACGAGGAGAAGAUGAAGGAGCUACAGGCUGUGCGUGAGACGCUGCUGCGGCAGCAUGAGGCUGAGCUGCUCAGGGUCAUCAAGAUCAAGGACAACGAGAACCAGCGGCUGCAGGCACUGCUCAGUGCCCUGCGUGAUGGCGGCCCCGAAAAGGUCAAGACCGUGCUGCUGUCCGAGGCCAAGGAGGAGGCCAAGAAGGGGUUCGAGGUGGAGAAGGUCAAGAUGCAGCAGGAGAUCUCCGAGCUCAAGGGCGCCAAAAGGCAGGUGGAGGAGGCGCUGACGCUGGUGAUCCAAGCGGACAAGAUCAAGGCCGCAGAGAUCCGCAGCGUGUACCACCUGCACCAGGAGGAGAUCACCCGCAUCAAGAAGGAGUGCGAGCGGGAGAUCCGCAGGCUGAUGGAGGAGAUAAAAUUUAAAGACAGAGCAGUCUUCGUGCUGGAGAGAGAGUUAGGGGUUCAAGCCGGGCAUGCUCAGAGACUGCAGCUCCAAAAAGAGGCUCUAGAUGAGCAGCUGUCCCAGGUCCGAGAGGCCGACCGGCACCCGGGCAGCCCCAGACGGGAACUUCCUCAUGCAGCUGGUGCAGGAGACGCUUCAGACCACUCGGGAAGCCCUGAACAGCAGUUGGAUGAAAAAGAUGCCCGGCGCUUCCAGCUUAAAAUCGCGGAGUUAAGUGCGAUUAUCCGCAAACUGGAGGACCGCAAUGCAUUGCUGUCGGAAGAGAGGAAUGAGCUGUUGAAGCGCGUAAGAGAAGCUGAGAGUCAGUACAAGCCUCUGCUGGAUAAAAACAAGCGCCUCAGUCGGAAGAACGAGGAUUUGUCUCAUGCUUUACGCCGAAUGGAAAACAAGUUAAAAUUUGUCACCCAGGAGAACAUAGAAAUGAGACAGAGAGCUGGAAUCAUACGGAGACCCAGUUCCUUGAAUGACCUUGAUCAAAGUCAGGAUGAGAGAGAAGUCGAUUUCUUGAAGCUUCAGAUUGUGGAGCAGCAAAACCUCAUAGAUGAACUGUCUAAGACCCUUGAGACCGCCGGCUACGUGAAGAGCGUGUUAGAGCGGGACAAGCUGUUAAGAUUCCGGAAGCAAAGAAAGAAAAUGGCAAAACUUCCCAAGCCGGUGGUUGUGGAGACCUUCUUUGGAUACGACGAAGAGGCUUCCCUGGAAUCCGACGGCUCCUCCGUCUCUUACCAAACAGACAGGACGGACCAGACCCCGUGCACCCCGGACGAUGACUUGGAGGAGGGCAUGGCCAAGGAGGAGACGGAGCUGAGGUUCCGGCAGCUGACCAUGGAGUACCAGGCCCUGCAGCGUGCCUACGCUUUGUUGCAGGAGCAGGUUGGAGGGACGCUGGACGCAGAGCGAGAAACCCGUGAGCAGCUACAAGCCGAAGUGCAGAGGGCACAGGCGCGGAUAGAGGACCUGGAGAAGGCCCUGGCGGAGCAGGGGCAGGAUAUGAAGUGGAUUGAAGAGAAGCAGGCACUGUACCGGAGAAAUCAAGAGCUUGUGGAAAAGAUCAAACAAAUGGAGACGGAAGAGGCUCGGCUCAGACACGAGGUGCAGGACGCCAGAGACCAAAACGAGCUGCUGGAGUUCAGGAUCCUGGAGCUUGAGGAGAGGGAGAGGAAGUCACCCGCCAUCAGCUUCCACCACACGCCCUUCGUGGACGGGAAGAGCCCCCUCCAGGUGUACUGCGAGGCCGAAGGUGUGACGGACAUUGUGGUUGCGGAGCUGAUGAAGAAGCUGGACAUCCUGGGCGAUAACGCCGUAAGUAACCUGACCAAUGAGGAGCAGGUGGUUGUCAUACAAGCCAGGACAGUCCUGACCUUGGCCGAAAAGUGGCUCCAGCAGAUUGAGGAGACAGAGGCGGCGCUGCAGCGGAAGAUGGUGGAUCUGGAGAGCGAGAAGGAGCUGUUCAGUAAGCAGAAGGGCUACCUGGACGAGGAGCUGGACUACCGGAAACAGGCCUUGGACCAGGCCAACAAGCACAUCCUGGAGCUGGAAGCCAUGCUGUAUGAUGCCCUGCAGCAGGAGGCCGGGGCUAAGGUGGCUGAGCUGCUGUCAGAGGAGGAGCGCGAGAAGCUCAAGGUGGCCGUGGAGCAGUGGAAGCGCCAGGUCAUGAGUGAGCUGCGCGAGCGGGACGCCCAGAUCCUGCGGGAGCGCAUGGAGCUGCUGCAGCUGGCUCAGCAGAGAAUUAAAGAGUUAGAAGAAAGAAUAGAAGCUCAGAAGAGACAAAUAAAGGAACUGGAGGAAAAGUUUCUAUUUUUGUUCUUAUUUUUCUCCUUAGCUUUCAUUCUCUGGUCAUAGUCCGUCUUGGCACCCUGACGUGCCCCACAUUGAAUCGGACCCUUUUCCUCCAGUGGGACCAGAAAGCAGGGACAAAAUGGGACGUCGCGUCUCCAUCCUGAAGACCCAGGGAGAUUUGGUCUCUGCACGCCCGUCCCGUGGAGGAAGAGUGAGAAGGGGCAGUGUGUGGGGCGUGGAGCUGCCGUCCACGUGGGAUGUGCCAGAACUAGAACUGGCUCUGCCGACUUCUCGGGGGCUUCUCCGGGACGGGCCUGGCCUUGGCUGCUGGACCCUGGGUCCCUUCUCCCGGACGGCAGCCCCCAUCCCAUUUCCAGGGAUGUGUAGCAUUCCCUGCCAAGCAGGGGUGAGAACUGCUUCUGUGCAGAAGCACCAGCCGCGGGUCCCCUCCUCUCUCUUGGUUCUCACAGUAGCUGCCACUGGUGUCUGGAGGAAGAUUUUCAGAAACAACAGAGGCUUGGCCUGAUGACAAGAUGAAAGCUGGACGGUGACCUUCAUUCAGGGGAACCUGGAGGCUCCCUGGGAUGGUCCUGGGAGGGCUCCCCGACGCCUCAGGGGCCCCUCCGAUGCUGCAAUAUGUUGCUGGGGUCCUGAGCACCCGCUGGCCAACAGACCCCACAUCCACCCUCGUUCAUCAUCAUCUCUGUGGGGACAGACAAGAGCCGUGGCCGCCGCGGGCCGCGUGGUGCCAUCAACCCUCUGCCUCCCUACUCAACCUGAGACAGGAAGGCCAAGAUCCCGCCCAAGCCGCCAGCUGGGAGCACCGCGGGACUGAGCCAAGGAAGGCGUGGGGAGCGUGGUGACAGGAGGUGGGACGAGGGGGCGGAGCUGGCUGGAACACGGAUGCCAGAGGCUGCCUCCAUAGUGAAUCUCCAGAAGUCACAGAGGCCCUGGGCACCCAGAGCCACCCAGCCUGGAAGCCCCUGCACGGGCCAGCCCUGCAGGCCAUGGACCCCGGCGGGCACCGAAGCCUCACCCCAAGCCUUUGCACACAAGGAGCAGCCCAGGUGGGGAUGGCGGGCGCAAGAAGGGAACCGCGGGGACGGCCUUUCCCCUCCCGCCCUGUGUGGGGACGCUGCACGAGCCGUGGACCAAGAGGCUGACAGGUCCCCUGGGGCGCGUUCUUCAGGUGCGUGGUGGACGAGGCGGCGUCCUCGCGGGGUCGGGACCUGGGUACCCAGCAGCAUCUGGCUCCUGCAUCCACCAAGGGCGCCCAGGCACAGCCUCAGGCCAGAAGGUUCGCUGCAGAGGUUCAUUCUAGAAGGAGCGGGAGACCAGCAGUCCCAGCCCUGUCCAAGGACGCCCGCUGCUUGGCACACGAGGGCGCCGCAGGCCCACCAUCCCUCAGGACAUGGCUGCCGAGUCCCCAGAGACUUCUGGUCCCACAGCAAGAGCUGGAGCUCCAAGCAUAACAUCUCUAACUGUGCGGCAAGGACAGCGCAGCCAGAGGUCGGGAGCUCCACAGCCUCCAGGGUCCCCCGAGGGCGGCUGGGGACAGGGAACGCCCCACAGCACAACAACACACACGGCGUGGACAUACGCACCUCCCCGCCAUACGAACCUCCCCGCGGAGGCUUCCCGGCUGCCUCACUCCCACCCCCUGCGGGCCAGGCCUCACAGCAGGGGCAGGUGGACCAUCCAGGCCAUGCUAAGCCCCGAGCAGGUUCCCACAACAGGUCACAGAGGGGACGCCGGGUCAGGAGAUGGGGGCCUGGGGAGCAAGGCCCCCCACAGCUGCCCUCGGUGACAUCUGGGACUUGGACAUCCAUGGACGGCAUCCCUGGAUGGAGCCAUUUCCUGGGUACUGGACCUGGAGGUGACUCGGAGCUUCUCCUGCUCCCAGCGUGUGUCCAUGGGGGCGGUCAGGGUAGACAGGCCACACCGUCAUCAGGGAGGGGCAGCCGGCCGCCAACGUGCAGACUGUGUCUCAGGCCUGUCGGCAUGGCGGGGACAGAGGUGGGUGGGCGCCGCUCCGCUCGGGGGCUGACAAGCCACAGGCUCAUUGUGGACAAGGCGUCUGUACAGCUCCGCACAGAAGACUUCUCAGCCAGUCCCGUCAGCCUCCCGGGAUCAGGGAGUGAGCCUCGAAUGCUAGAUCAGAAAGGAAAACAGAGGAAGCAGUGCAUUGGUGAAGGCAACGUUAGGUGUGAUUUCCAUUCCUGCUGGGAGACCCGGGACGCAGCCCGGGAGCUUCGUCCAGCCUGUGGAUGGAGCCUGACUGGCUGCAGAUGGAACUUCUGUGUCCUCCCACCCUAGGUGGGCUAAGGUUCUGCUCUCAGAGCUGAAUUGACAGGAGGUGUGUGUGUGUGCUCACUUGUGUGCACAAGCAUGCGUUUAUGCAUGUUUUCACGCAACCAGAAGAGCCAUUCGUGGGAUUUAGCCAUUUCGAGGCACCUAGAAGUUGAGGCAGCCAGCUGUGCAGCCAGGUGUGACUGUUACUGGCAGCAUUGUAUAAAAGACACGACUCAGCUGCCGUAGGGAGGACUGGGUUGUCUGGAAGUAUUAGGCUCAUUUUAUAUUUGUGUCAGAAGAAAUGUCUGACUUUGGGGCAGAUGACACGGUGGCUGCGGACCAGGCAUGGCUCCCUAGGUUGAAAUCAGGGAAAAGCUAAUAGUAUCAGACAGAUAUGCUUUUUCUUUGGUGGCUGCAGGAUUUUUGCUGGAAAAUGCACUAUUAAUCAGCACUUGUCCAAGAAAGACCCAUCCAUUUCUGUUGUCAUUCAAGCCACAGUUCCUGAUUUACUCGGCAAGAUACUGGGCCAGUUCAGUGUCUCUAGCUGAGCCUGACCUCGGGGUUUGCGUCUCGAGUCUGAAAUCCUGUUUAGUCCUCUGUGCAUAGUUUUGUCUCAUUUUAACGACUGCAUCUUCUUGGCACAUUUAUUAUACUCACAACUGAAUGGCACACAAUAGCCUUGUGUUAAUAAAAGCUACCGUGGCGCUGUGGGUGAACCGCUGGGUUGAAGUCCGAUGGACUCUACGAUGCAGGCAUCCAGAAAUAUGUUGUAACUCUACCUGGCUCCCUGCCAGCCUGGCCUCCUCCUCUGGGAGAGCUCCUGGCAUGGUCCCAAUGUGUACCUGCAUGGGAACAACAGCUGCAUGGGCCAGCUGUUUCGGAUCUAAAGAUGUGCAGUGAAACUCACAUUCCCAGAUUCACAUCCCUCAUGUUUAUUUGGGUCAUCAUGGUUUAGCAUGUUGUAUAUAUGUCUGGAGCACUUCAUACACCUCUAUCCACCACAGACACUCUUAAUCACAGUUCUGUAAUAAUAAUAAGGCAAACUAUACGGCAAAGAGAAGCAUGUAAAUAUGUACCAAAUCCUUAUGAAGUUGUAAUUGUUUAUAUGUAAAAAGUAUGUAUAUAGGAACGGGAGAAGGUGCAAGGAAUGUGCUGAAUAACAUCCAAACUGCAUCGCGUCUCUGCCCCAUUCCUGAAAGCACACAUCUAGUUGGAGCGUCAGUUCCUCUCCUUAGAUAUCAUUGUUUUCACUCGUCUAUCAUAGGCACCUUCUUUACAUCUGAUUACAAUACCCAGCAUUUCAGAACUGGGUUUUUGCCCCCAAAAAGGUAAAUAUGAGCAUUUAUCACUGACUCCUCCUGGUCCAGUGAGCAGCAGCAGAAUUCAAGUAUUUAAAAAUAAGGUGCAUUUCUAAAUUGCAGGCUAUACCUUCUUUUCCAAACCAAUGGGCUAGAGUGAAUUUCCUCCAAGUACUUGGGCUGUCUUACUGCUAGCUCUUCUAACAGGGGAAGUCUGUAUGAAUGCAUCACCCCCUAAUAAGGCAAGAGGAAGGACCCUGAAAUGUUGCCAGAAAUGUACUGUUACAUCAACAUUUACAUUAUAUUAACAUCAUCACACUCUGUGUUCAACACACAGAACAACAUAGAUACUUUAGUUUGUCUAAAGUAAAAAUCCACAUAAAUAGCAGAUUCCUUUGUUGACACCAGUGUGUUGUUUACCUUGUGCCCAUGGUCCAGAUUUUGAGCUGGAGAAGGACUAUGGCUGUUCCUUAAAGUCUCUGCCCUUGCAGAAUCUGUAGCCUUCAGGAUACCCCGAGUGCCUUACAGGGCUUGUGAACACCGAUACUAGAAGUCAAAAAGAAGAGAGUGCCCAAGUGUGGGUUUGGAGGCACUGACGCAUUCGCCAACUCACCGUCAUCCCAUCCUUGAAACCCUGAGAGAGAGUGUGUGUUUUAUCACAGUAAUGGAAUUCAGUUUAGCCUCAGGAAACUCAUAUUGUGAAUAUAGGUAUCAAAUCAUAUAUUUGUUUACUGUAUAUUUUUUAAAAAGCUUUAUUGUAAAUUUAUGCAAAAACUAACCGGGCCUGUUUUCUUACGGCGGCAUGCCAGGUAGUGUGUGUAUUCUCCCAGGCACUCCCUUCAUAGUCACCCUCUAACCACGUGACAUUCCGUUCCAUGCUAAGCAGUAUUCACAGGCCUAAAAUAGGUUUGUAUGGUGAUCUACAAGAUUUUACAAAUAUUUUUGUAUUGUGAUUCCUAUGAUAUAUACCAGAGAAUUUUUUACUCGUUUGUAAAUUAUUGUACAGUUUUAAUAAAAAAUGUUUUAAAUCUUAGACGAUUAAAGUCCCCUCAAAGGUAUUAAAGUUUGAACUGAAAGCCGUA